GCUGCGGUGGCAAUGGCGGCGCCCCCUGCACCAGCCGCCAAGGGGUCCCCGCAGCCGGAGCCGCACGCCCCAGAGCCCGGCCCGGGGAGCGCCAAGCGAGGGCGAGAGGACAGCAGAGCCGGUCGCCUCUCAUUCUGUACAAAGGUGUGCUAUGGCAUUGGUGGGGUCCCCAACCAGAUAGCCUCCAGCGCCACAGCCUUUUACCUGCAGCUUUUCCUGCUUGAUAUAGCACAGAUCCCUGCCGCCCAGGUGUCACUUGUUCUGUUUGGGGGAAAAGUGUCUGGGGCGGCUGCUGACCCUGUGGCUGGGUUCUUCAUCAACAGGAGCCAGAGGACAGGGUCUGGACGGCUCAUGCCUUGGGUGCUGGGCUGCACCCCCUUCAUCGCCCUGGCCUACUUCUUCCUGUGGUUCCUGCCCCCCUUCACCAGCCUGCGAGGCCUCUGGUACACGACUUUCUACUGCCUGUUCCAGGCCCUGGCCACGUUCUUCCAGGUGCCCUACACAGCGCUCACCAUGCUGCUGACUCCCUGCCCAAGGGAGCGGGACUCGGCCACCGCCUACCGGAUGACUGUGGAGAUGGCGGGAACACUGAUGGGGGCCACUGUCCACGGGCUCAUCGUGUCCGGCGCCCACAGACCCCACAGGUGCGAGGCCACUGCGACCCCGGGGCCAGUCACUGUCUCCCCGAAUGCAGCCCAUCUCUACUGCAUUGCGGCUGCCGUGGUUGUAGUGACUUACCCCGUGUGCAUCAGUUUACUGUGCCUAGGGGUGAAGGAGCGGCCAGACCCCUCUGCCCCAGCCUCAGGCCCAGGCUUGAGUUUCCUGGCUGGGCUGAGCCUCACUACCCGGCACCCACCCUACCUGAAGCUGGUGAUCUCCUUCCUGUUCAUCUCUGCUGCUGUUCAGGUGGAGCAGAGCUACCUGGUCCUGUUCUGUACACAUGCCUCCCAGCUACACGACCACGUCCAGGGCCUGGUACUAACUGUCCUGGUCUCAGCCGUGCUGAGCACCCCGCUGUGGGAGUGGGUUCUCCAGCGCUUUGGGAAGAAGACGUCAGCCUUUGGGAUCUUUGCGAUGGUGCCCUUUGCGAUCUUGCUGGCUGCUGUGCCCACAGCACCUGUGGCAUAUGUCGUGGCCUUUGUAUCUGGCGUGAGCAUUGCUGUGUCCUUGCUGCUACCCUGGUCCAUGCUGCCAGACGUGGUGGAUGACUUUCAGCUGCAGCACCGUCACGGGCCAGGCCUGGAGACCAUCUUCUACUCCUCCUACGUCUUCUUCACCAAGCUGUCUGGCGCAUGUGCCCUGGGCAUCUCCACCCUCAGUCUGGAGUUCUCGGGGUAUAAGGCAGGGGUCUGCAAGCAAGCAGAGGAGGUGGUGGUCACCCUCAAAGUCCUCAUUGGCGCCGUGCCCACCUGCAUGAUCCUUGCUGGGCUCUGCAUCCUCAUGGUCGGCUCCACUCCAAAGACACCCAGUCGGGACGCCUCCAGCCGGCUGAGCCUUCGGAGGAGGACCAGCUACAGCCUGGCCUAAAGCUUAGGAGGGCGACUGUGAAUGGACACAGGAGCCAGCACCCUCGGGGCCUGACAUCGCCCUCCUCAGCCCUCCAGCACCUGGUCUGGCAGUUUAGUAUGUGACCUUUCUCCCUGGGAUGUGGAGUCUUCGGCAACGUGUCCUGAAGGGACUGGCCCGCACUCCAGGACCCCACUUGGCAUUUCUUGUCUGUUGCCUUCAGACUAUCUCAGAUAGGCCUGUGCCCCUGACUAGCCCAGUAGCACUUGUCUCUAGAAAAAGGAAGCUCCUGCCCAACCUGGCUUGUGGACCAGUAAUAUCUGUGGCCUACCACCCAUUCAAGAAAACGUUACAGCCGGCUCACUGCAAAAUCCGCCUCCCGGGUUCACGCCAUUCUCCUGCCUCAGCCUCCCGAGUAGCUGGGACUACAGGUGCCCGCCACCACGCCCAGCUAAUUUUUGUAUUUUUAGUAGAGACGGGGUUUCACCGUGUUAGCCAGAAUGGUUUCGAUCUCCUGACCUCGUGAUCCGCCCCGCCUCAGCCUCCCAAAGGCAUGAGCCACCGUACUCGGCCUGCCCAGGCUGGUCUUAAACUCCUGGCCUCAGGUGAUCCUACUGCCUCAGCCUCCUGAGUAGCUGGGAUUACAGACACAGCCCCCGUUCCCAGCUCUAGCAUUUCUUAAGGACAAAAUUGGUGUGUAAGUAACAGGAAAUUCACAUUAUGCUGUACUCAUUCUCUAAUAUCACAGCCAUGUUAGAACAAAUUUGGGUUUUCAAAACAAGCGUAACUGAACAGAGUAUAUAUAUGUAUGUAUAUAAAUAUAUAGAAAUCCUAAAUGGUCCCUGUGACAUAAGAAAUACACAUUUGGUCUCUGCCCCAGGUUCCUGGCACAGAGCUUCUAAAAUGCUAGUAACUUCCUGAGUGGUAGGGGUGAGGGGAACAUCUUUUGUUAUACAUAAGAAGCCCUUUUCAAACAGAUCUGAGUUUAUGCUAAUGAUGUGACUGGCAGAGGAUGGGGGCUGGUUGCCAGAGAAACCAACCAUGUGAUUAGAAGGUUGAAACUUUCAGCCUUAUCUUCCUACCGGGAGGGGACAGGGGCUGAAGACUGAGCUCAUCAUCAAUGAUUUAAUCAAUUGUGCCCAUGUAAUGGAGCCUCCACUUCCAAACGAAGGGUUUCAGAGAGCUUCUAGGUUGGUGAACACAUCCAUGUACCAGGAGGUCUACCCCACUCCACGGGGACAGAAACUCUUGUGUAGGGGACCCUUUUAGAUUUCAUUCUAUAUACCUCUUCAGCUGGCUGUUCAUUUUAUAAUCAACCAAUAAAUGUUAAGUAAAGUGUU